GAGGCCCUCUGGAGGAUUAUAAGAACGGAGGGCCUAUGGAGGCCCAUGAGGGGGCUGAACGUCACAGCAACAGGCGCAGGGCCUGCCCACGCCCUUUAUUUUGCCUGCUACGAAAAGUUAAAAAAGACAUUGAGUGAUGUAAUCCACCCUGGGGGCAAUAGCCAUAUUGCCAAUGGUAUUGAGCCUUCCUGUGCUGGUUCCCCCACUUUCCCAACUCUUUGGGCUUUGCUGCUGUCAGUGCUUUCCAGUCUCAGCAUGGUUUGGAGCUGAAGCUUUGGGCUGGGAUAGGCCAGAUUAUAAGGGAGGGACUUCCAAACCUGAUGUUCUCAGACAACGGGCCGCUUCAACCCUGCCUUUUCCUUUGGGGCACCUCAACAAAGGGUUACAGUAUCCUCCCUUACCUACCAGCUUGACUUGUUCCUCUCAUCUCCCUGGCAUCAACUUCUAAUGCCCUGGUAAUGUGGAGACACACUGAACUACCCCCAGUCUAUGUUUGACAGUUGGGUGGUGUCCUGCUCCUUAGGGCAGGAUUGGAGGCGACCCAGCCAGCCACCCAAGGAAGAUACUAAUGAAGCCCCUGCUUUUUGCCUCACCUUUUCAGGAUCCCAACUCACCAGAGGCAGUUUGUGUUGAGAACAUGACAAAGCCUCAUGACAAAAUGAAUGGGGGUGGGGCCAAGGAACUGCAUGAAGAAACCAGAAGGUUGUGUGGAAGUGCGGCCGGGUGUGUGGCAACAUUACUUCAUGAUGCAGCCAUGAACCCUGCGGAAGUGGUCAAGCAGAGGAUGCAGAUGUACAACUCACCAUACCACCGGGUGACAGACUGUGUACGGGCAGUGUGGCAAAAUGAAGGGGCCGGGGCCUUUUACCGCAGCUACACCACCCAGCUGACCAUGAACGUUCCUUUCCAAGCCAUUCACUUCAUGACCUAUGAAUUCCUGCAGGAGCACUUUAACCCCCAGAGACGGUACAACCCAAGCUCCCACGUCCUCUCUGGAGCUUGCGCAGGAGCUGUAGCUGCCGCAGCCACAACCCCACUGGACGUUUGCAAAACACUGCUCAACACCCAGGAGUCCUUGGCUUUGAACUCACACAUUACAGGACAUAUCACAGGCAUGGCUAGUGCCUUCAGGACGGUAUAUCAAGUAGGUGGGGUGACCGCCUAUUUCCGAGGGGUGCAGGCCAGAGUAAUUUACCAGAUCCCCUCCACAGCCAUCGCAUGGUCUGUGUAUGAGUUCUUCAAAUACCUAAUCACUAAAAGGCAAGAAGAGUGGAGGGCUGGCAAGUGAAGUAGCACUGAACGAAGCCAGGGGUUCAGAUGACACUGCUGCAUCCUGGUCACAUUCUCUGUCUCCUGGAAUGCUCCCACCUCAAGUGGAGUUAGAAGGAAGGUAGAGGGGCUCUCCCCCAGGAUUUUGGUGUUUUGACUAACACCAGUUCCUGCCAACCUCUGUUGCCACCACCUUUCCUUCCAGGCCCUAAGCACGUGCAGCAAAGCACACCACAGCACCUUUGAUAACCUCUCUCCAUCCUGGGCCUGAUGACCUGCUCUAGACUGUUAUAGAGGGAUAAGCAGCUCAUUCCCCUGGUUCCUAAUAAAAAGCCUUUAAAUUAAA